ACUUUUGAUGGGUUCCGGGUCCCAAAAGGGUUCGAGGCCUCUUGCCUUCGCUCCGUAGGAGGGAGUUCUCUUCUGGCCCUGGGGGCCGCAGGACUGUCCAGGAAUACAGUUUCCAGGUGAGAUCUUACUUGAAACACCGGUAGUUCUAGCACAGCUAAAAUGGCAUCUACUUGGGCUAUCCAGGCCCACAUGGACCAGGAUGAACCUUUGGAAGUAAAGAUAGAGGAAGAGAAAUAUACCACCAGACAGGAUUGGGACCUGCGUAAAAACAACACCCAUAGCAGAGAGGUCUUCCGUCAGUACUUCAGACAGUUCUGCUACCAGGAGACAUCUGGUCCCCGUGAGGCUUUGAGCCGACUCCGAGAACUUUGCCAUCAGUGGCUGAGGCCAGAGACCCACACCAAAGAACAGAUUCUGGAGCUGCUGGUGCUGGAGCAGUUCCUGACCAUCCUACCUGAGGAGCUCCAGGCCUGGGUGCAGGAGCAGCAUCCAGAGAGUGGGGAGGAGGUGGUGACUGUGCUGGAGGAUUUAGAGAGAGAACUGGAUGAACCAGGAGAGCAGGUCUCAGUCCACACUGGGGAACAGGAAAUGUUCUUGCAGGAGACGGUACGUCUACGAAAAGAAGGAGAACCCAGUAUGUCCCUCCAGUCCAUGAAAGCCCAGCCAAAGUAUGAAUCUCCAGAACUUGAAUCCCAACAGGAGCAAGUUUUAGAUGUUGAGACUGGAAAUGAGUAUGGGAAUUUAAAGCAAGAAGUUUCUGAAGAAAUGGAACCACAUGGGAAGACAUCCAGUAAAUUUGAAAAUGAUAUGUCCAAGUCUGCUAGGUGUGGAGAAACUCGUGAACCUGAAGAAAUAACAGAAGAGCCCUCUGCUUGCUCCAGAGAAGAUAAACAACCUACCUGUGAUGAAAAUGGAGUAAGCCUGACUGAGAACUCUGACCAUACUGAACAUCAGAGAAUCUGUCCAGGAGAAGAAUCUUACGGAUGUGAUGACUGUGGAAAAGCUUUUAGUCAGCACUCACACCUCAUAGAACAUCAGAGGAUCCAUACUGGAGAUAGACCCUACAAAUGCGAAGAAUGUGGAAAAGCUUUCCGUGGGAGAACUGUGCUUAUUCGACACAAAAUAAUACACACUGGAGAGAAACCGUAUAAGUGUAAUGAAUGUGGCAAAGCCUUUGGCCGGUGGUCAGCUCUUAACCAACAUCAGAGACUUCACACAGGAGAAAAACACUAUCACUGUAAUGACUGUGGCAAAGCCUUUAGUCAGAAAGCAGGCCUCUUUCACCAUAUCAAGAUCCACACAAGAGACAAACCUUAUCAGUGCACUCAGUGUAAUAAAAGUUUUAGUCGGCGUUCCAUACUUACUCAGCAUCAAGGAGUUCAUACCGGCGCCAAGCCGUAUGAGUGCAACGAGUGUGGAAAAGCCUUUGUUUAUAACUCAUCCCUUGUUUCCCAUCAGGAAAUCCACCACAAAGAAAAAUGCUAUCAGUGUAAGGAAUGUGGGAAAUCCUUCAGUCAGAGUGGCCUUAUUCAGCAUCAGAGAAUUCACACUGGGGAAAAACCCUACAAAUGUGACGUAUGUGAAAAAGCCUUUAUUCAAAGGACAAGUCUUACAGAACAUCAGCGAAUUCACACUGGAGAAAGACCCUAUAAAUGUGAUAAGUGUGGGAAGGCGUUUACUCAAAGAUCAGUCCUCACGGAACAUCAGAGAAUCCACACUGGAGAGAGGCCCUACAAGUGUGAUGAGUGUGGGAAUGCCUUCCGAGGAAUCACCAGCCUCAUUCAGCAUCAGAGAAUCCACACUGGGGAGAAGCCCUACCAAUGUGAUGAGUGUGGAAAAGCCUUCAGACAGAGGUAAACAAGACAUUAAGUGUUUAAGGCAAAAAGCAUGGAGAGGUUGGGGAAGAGCCAAGUUUCUAAAGUAAUGAAAAGUGAGGUGAGUUUCAACACGGGCUAUGAAUGAAAACGUAACCUGACAAUCAAACUGAUUCCAGAGAGUGCAGUGGGAAGUGACUGCAGAGGAAAAAAGAAUGGGGCCCUCCUUCCAAAAAUAAAUUGUAUUAAGAGGUUGCCAGAGUUUGAGGUACGAGAUGAAGCUAAUGAGGAAAGACAGUGGGAUUGAGCAGGGCUCCAAAUUGAGACAUCUCAACUGUAUAAUGAGGUUGGUUGUAGAGACCUCUAAGAUAGAAGAACUUAGACAAGUCUGCAUUCCUGUAUUCAGUACAGAAGUAGCCACUUUUGUUAAUAUACAGAUUAUUUGUAGAGUUGUUAUAGUCAAAACAAAGCUGUUCUUAUUGGCCAUCUUUUGGAAUUGAGAAAAGGAUUUAUUAAUGACAAUACCGCACACUUAUUAGCUGCUUACUAAGGGCCAGACAUUACUAAAUGCUUUACUUACAACAUUUCACUUUCAGCUGGGGAAACUGAAAUAGAUAAUCUAAAGCUGCUCAAGGUCCCGAAGUUAGUAUGUGGUCAGGCCAAGAUUUGAACCCAAGCAGCCCAGUUCCAGAGUUCACACUUUUAACCUCUGUGAUACACUUCCUCUCUUUAUUUCAGUUGAACAAACCAUGUGUUGCAGUGGUAAUUCAGUGUCUUGAGUAAUUAUCUGUAAAAACUUUUUAUCUCCAGUCAUUAUUCUGAAAAAUGAUUCAGAAAGUCCUGGAGUCCAAACACCUCAGGUAAUAAUAUUAUCACCCCCUCUGCAUACCAAAUCUUGGAUGAGGUUUGGCCAGCAUAAACAGCUCUACUUCUUGUUGCCUGCACAGUGAGGGUGUCACAGGAGACAUUCCACUUUAAAAAUGGGCUCUUUAUAUGAAAAGAUCACCCUUCUUAGAAUGAUAAAUCACUCUGCAUUAUUCUCACAGAAUAAGGAAUAUUUGGCUGUCUAAUUUAAUACAGAAAGAUUUAAAGAUUUGUCCCCAAGUGUUGAUAACCCAUUAUGGAUCUAUCUUUAAUGCCAGUUUUCAAAAGUGAUUUUAUAUUAGAAGAUACUUCUUGGAUUUAAAAAUGCACACACACACAUAUAUGUGAUAUAUGAUAUUUUUCUUUGCUUAAGACUUACCAAUUUUACAGUUCAAAUGGUGACCCUCCUAACUCCACAAGGCCAGAAUUUGAGCAAAUGCUUGUUGUUCAACCUAGACAUAAUCAUUCGAUAGCCUUUAAUUGAAUCUCUUCCCAACUUUUAUCCUUUAAACCGAAAAGUUAUAUACCACAGUCACUACAGCAGCUCAUUUUAUUGGAAUUUCUUUGGAUCCUCUCCCUCUCAAACGUUCUGUGUGCGUUUGGUAAGGAGUCCUCACACAUUAUUUUUUACUUGUAUAGUAUUUCUACAUAUAUAUAUAAAUGUGUAAAAAGUAUGUAUGAAUAUUUUUGUGUUGUAAUUUGUAUUUUACAUAUAUAUGACCUCAUGUAUAUAAUUUGAUGUUGACAAAGCCAACUAUGAUAAGUGUUUUAAACUUUUCAGUUGAUUAGCCCCCUAGCUUACAUUGUAAGACCAUCAUUUAGAGCCAGCAGUUUUCCCUUGAUUUCAUCUCUUGAAGAGACAGUUGAUUCUCUUCAUACACGUUAAAAACACCAUUUAGGUGUCAGAAACCCAUCAGUCAAGGCUCCCAGAGCUUUCACCUAUCAUAGUUCAAGUUAAUCUCUAGGGUAUAUGUCUGUUUGCUCCUGCCAGUCAUUUUCCUAAGCCCAGUUGGCCUGCUCCUGGAAGUCCCAAGAAGGGCUCCAUAGUGGAAGCCAUUUGUUACUUUUGAUUUAUGAUUACAUCAUCAUUACUCCUCUUCAAGCUUAGUGGGCAUAUCUUAGUGUUUUGAUCUAGUGCCUUAGUUCUGCCUACUUCAGUAACGAAUUUAGGAGUAGAUGUCUCCUCAUUUCAUCCCUGAUAAAGAUUGAGGCAGUUUAGGGACUCUGCAGCUUCCUCUGGCCAAAUUCCCUACUUAUUCCUGAGAUAGGGUUUAAGAACCUGGAUUCUAGAGACGGAUUGCCAUGGUUCGAAUCUCAGUUUACUAGCUAAGUGACUUUGGGCAAGGGAUUUAACCUCUCGUCCCUCAGUUUCCUCCUAUGUAAAAUGACAAGGAUAAUAGUACCAACCCAAUGUAGAUUAAAUGAGUUUACGAAGUGUUAGAAUAGUGCUUGGCACAUUAGUGCUUUACAACUGCUAUUUUGAUUGUUGUUGUGGGCUCUCUCAAAUGCAUUGUCUCUAGAUGCCAGUGACCCAGGUCAAAAUUUACCUUUAACCAAGCUGCAUGUUUCCCAGACUGCUGCACAGUCCUCCUAGCCCUGAGAUAAAAGCUCCCACCCAGGUAUACUUUUACUUUCCUGCUGGAGAACUGAUGAGCAGUGGCCAGCAGGGGACACUUAUCGCCCAAGCUGGAAAGGAGAGAUUUCUUCCCUUUUGUCUCCGCCCCUGUUAGUUAUCAGAGGUACCUAGCGGCCCCUGCUAUCCGAAGUUUGCCUUCCGAGCUGCUCUUCCGACGUUCUGCAGCUGGAAGGCCGGCCUCGCACGGGUCUGACGCGCCCCGGCCUGGGAGCAUGGGCCCCUGGGGUUACCUGACUGCUCAGCUGGAACUUGCGCUGCUCAGCUGGGGCGGGGUUCGGCCGGGCAACCACAGAGAGGAGAAAGCCUCCAGAAUCCUAGAGAAGCUGAAUGCUGAGACAGCCGUUGACGGCAGCGGCACGUGAAAGUACCGACCUUUCUGGCCUUUGUGACGGACCUUUGGAGGCGGGUGGUUUCAGAUUCGUGCGCUCCGGCCUUUCAGUGUCUCUGGUGAGGUUGGGCCUGAUAGGUUGAGAGCUGCCAGGGGAAGUUAAGGAUGACUUCCAAGUUUUGAGGUAUCAGGAAAACUGGCUGUUGAGAAAAAGGAGUCUGGGUUCCCCGUUUGGUGAAAGGAAAGUUGGGUUCAUUUGGGGAAAUUAUGUGAUUCAUGAUUUUCCCAAGAUCGACGCUGAGUACAAGAAAAGACAGAAUCCACCUAGCUGUUGUGUGACUUUGAGCAAAUUACUUAAUCUCUCUGUGCCUCAGUUUUAUUCCUCUGUCAGUGAGAUUAUAAGUGUCUACUUAAAUGGCUGCAUGCAUGGUGCAUUUUAAAUAAAUAUUAGCUGUUGUUAUUUUUCAUUUCUGAUGUUCUUAUCUCUGCCGUUUAUACAGGAUAUUGCAUGUAUGGUGCAUUUUAAAUAAAUAUUAGCCGUUGUUAUUUUUCAUUUCUGAUGUUCUUAUCUCUGCCGUUUAUAUGGGUAUUUUGAAGUGGGGGGGAGCCAAGGGAAGAGGGUCAUGAUCUUUAAAGUUUUAUUAAUAAAAACUUUUAGAGAGUAAAAGGCUAGCAGAUGGGGCUAGCUAAUAAUUUGCAGUCACUUUUGCUUUCCUAAUUUAUUUACCUUCCUGACAGAGUUCCGUUUUCUUUCAGUGCCUUGUUCAGAUAAGUGAGUUCUUGGCUAAAGAAGUAAACAAAAUUUAGCUUCUGUUAACAUUGUUAUUUUAUGCCUCAGGAAGAAGACCAGCUACAAGGAAAUACUUCUGAAAAAUCACUCUGAACCCCAAGCUGGAGUGAAUCUUCUCCUGAGCUCUCUCAUUCCAGAAUGGCAAUCUUGUUUCAGGAGAGAUCUCUAAUAGUGACUGAUGGUAAAGGAAGAAGGCUGUGCCUAGAACAAAGAAUCAGGCUGGCAAAGAAAUCACAGGUCUUUCCUCAAACUUUAAAUUGCUACUCUCUGGAGAUAGCUACCUGGACUUUACAGAGCUGUCAGAAGACUUGGGAAGGUUUGCCAGCAUUGGAAAAAGCCACUUGGACUUCACAGAGCUGUCAGAAGACUUAGGAAGCUUUGCCAGUAGUUCCUGAGACCAGAAAUACAUAUUAUGAAGCAGGUGCUGGAACAGGCCCUGGCCCCUACUUGUGAAGCUGCAGAUAUAGAUGGUGUUACUGAGAAGGAAACUAAGGACUUGGCUCCAAAACAAAACAAAACAAAAUCUGGAGAUGCUGAAUUUUGUUGGGGGGAAUGUCUGUAGAACUGCAACAUCAAUGCAGUAAGUGUAGUAAAAGCUUUAGUUUAUGGUGAGUCAUUACUCAGCAUCAUGGAGUCCACGAUGAAGAGAAUCUCUUUUCAAUCUGUGCAAUCAACAAGUUUUUGAAAGGCUUUUGUUUAUAGUGGAACCCUCUUUUCCCCCUAGAAGAACCACCACAAGGAAAAAUGCUGUCACCAUAAGGAAUGUGGGAAAGUUUUCAGCCACAUGGCCUUAUUUGACUUCAAAGAAUCCACAUGAGAGAGAGACUGCAUAAAUGUAAUAACUGAGGAGGCCUUUGUUCAGCAAAGAAACCUUAUACAAACUCGUAUAAAGAAUGUAGGAAGACCUUCACCCAGAAGCCAGGACUGACUGUGCACCAGAGAAUCUGCACAAUAAACAUGAUGAAUGUGGAGAUGCUUGCUUCAGCAUUGGAGAAUUCACAGUAAAGGGAAACCCUGCCAGUGUGAUGAGUACGGAAAAGUCUUCAGAGGUUGGAACUUGGGAAAAAUCAGUGAGUGAAUUCAUAUUAGAGAGGCUCUUAUAAAUGAGAGGAUUGUGGAAACUUGUAUAGACAGAGAUCAGACCUCAACAAGGGAGCCUCCACAGUAUUGAAAAGUUAAUAUAAUUAAUGUAAGUGGGCAAGUUGUAUGGGGAAUGGGUAGUCUAAAUUGCUCAUUUUAGCCAGUAAAAACAUUAAAUUAGUUUCUUAGAUCAAGAAAAGGAAAUGUUAGAAGUUAUUUUUCCCUUCCAGAGGGGUCUAUAUGUGUAAGCAACCAGGACUUUUGAAAUAAGUUGCAUCUCUGGAUUUGUGAUCUGUCUCCUGGAUGAUUAUCUCUGUUUUGGGAGACAGGUAUUUUUUCUUCAUGCCUGCUCUAGUCUCAUCUCAUAUCUUUAAUUCAUUCAGCAAGUAUACACAAUAGUAUUAUCGUCUACUGUUUGUUGUAAAUAUAUAUAUAUUAUUUUCUUUUUGGUCUGAGUAGGCUUGUAUUGGUACCCUAGGACAUAAAAAUCACAUAUAUCAUGUUUCAGUAAAUGCAGUGAAAGGAACUAUAUUAUUAAAUUGCUGGGAAUUUCUGUAAAUUUGAGACUACCUUUAUAUUCUCCAACACAAGACCGUGUAGGUGUCCCUUCAGAGAGUAUAUUUUUCUAGCUUGGCUUCUUUAUUUUCUUUAUUUUUUUGAGAUGGAGUCUUGCUCCUGUCGCCCAGGCUGGAGUGCAAUGGCACGAUCUCGGCUCACUGCAACCUCCGCCUCCCAGGUUCAAGUGAUUCUCCUGUCUCAGUCUCCCGAGUAGCUGGGAUUACAGGCACUUGCCACCAUUCCCAGCUAAUUUUUGUAUUUUUAGUAGAGACGGGGUUUCACCAUGUUGGCCAGGCUGGUCUCGAACUCCUGACCUUGUGAUCUGCCCACCUUGGCCUCCCAAAGUUCAGGGAUUACAGGCAUGAGCCACCAUGCCCGGCUGUUUUUUUAAGAUAGAAAAAUAUACUUCAUGUAUAGCCUAUUGACAGAUAAUGACUGAUAUUUUUUCUUAUAGAUAACACAUAAUAAACAUUGUGAAGACUAAUAAGUAACUUGCUUAUUCUUUUCAGUUCUAAAACCUGUAGGAAAGAAUCUUUAGAAGCUGUCAACAAGUUGAUAAUGUAGCCCAAUCUCUACCCAUGAUAGGAGAGUAAGGCUUAUAUAUUUUAUAGUAGGGCACUAAAUACAGGAACCAUGUAUUUAAAAACUUUUUAGUGAUUAUCUCAGAAUUCUAGGUGUCCCUCUGCUGUACAUCCCUAAAUUUUUUGCAUAGGUAUUAUUAAUAAAUUCAUUAUUUUCAAAGAUGGACUGUGUUCUGUAAAAAGCUUUUCCAGUAUCUGCAAAUCACACAGUUUUUUUUAACUCUAUUACUAUUAUAUAAAAUGAUUUCUUAAUAUUGAACCAACCUUGCAUUCCUAGAAUAAACCUCACUUAGCCAUGA